ACCAUCGAGCUUCGCGGGGUUGCUGGGCUGACGGAUCCGCGGGCCGGCAUCUGAAGCGAGCGGGACGCAGCGCGGCCAGGGCCUCCGGGCAUACGCAGGCUGGUCCCCAAGGCCCGCGGCCGCCGCCAUGUCGGUGCUGGGCGAGUACGAGCGACACUGCGAUUCCAUCAACUCGGACUUUGGGAGCGAGUCCGGGGGUUGCGGGGACUCGAGUCCGGGGCCUAGCGCCAGUCAGGGGCCGCGAGCCGGCGGCGGCGCGGCGGAGCAGGAGGAACUGCACUACAUCCCCAUCCGCGUCCUGGGCCGCGGCGCCUUCGGGGAAGCCACGCUGUACCGCCGCACCGAGGAUGACUCACUGGUUGUGUGGAAGGAAGUCGAUUUGACCCGGCUGUCUGAGAAGGAACGUCGUGAUGCCUUGAAUGAGAUUGUUAUUCUGGCACUGCUGCAGCACGACAACAUUAUUGCCUACUACAAUCACUUCAUGGACAAUACCACGCUGCUGAUUGAGCUGGAAUAUUGUAAUGGAGGGAACCUGUAUGACAAAAUCCUUCGUCAGAAGGACAAGUUGUUUGAGGAAGAGAUGGUGGUGUGGUACCUAUUUCAGAUUGUUUCAGCAGUGAGCUGCAUCCAUAAAGCUGGAAUCCUUCAUAGAGAUAUAAAGACAUUAAAUAUUUUUCUGACCAAGGCAAACCUGAUAAAACUUGGAGAUUAUGGCCUAGCAAAGAAACUUAAUUCUGAGUAUUCCAUGGCUGAGACGCUUGUGGGAACCCCAUAUUACAUGUCUCCAGAGCUCUGUCAAGGAGUAAAGUACAAUUUCAAGUCUGAUAUCUGGGCAGUUGGCUGCGUCAUUUUUGAACUGCUUACCUUAAAGAGGACGUUUGAUGCUACAAACCCACUUAACCUGUGUGUGAAGAUCGUGCAAGGAAUUCGGGCCAUGGAAGUUGACUCUAGCCAGUACUCUUUGGAAUUGAUCCAAAUGGUUCAUUCGUGCCUUGACCAGGAUCCUGAGCAGAGACCUACUGCAGAUGAACUUCUAGAUCGCCCUCUUCUCAGGAAACGCAGGAGAGAGAUGGAGGAAAAAGUCACUCUGCUUAAUGCACCUACAAAGAGACCAAGGUCAAGCACUGUGACUGAAGCACCCAUUGCUGUAGUAACAUCACGAACCAGUGAAGUCUAUGUUUGGGGUGGUGGAAAAUCCACCCCCCAGAAACUGGAUGUUAUCAAGAGUGGCUGUAGUGCCCGGCAGGUCUGUGCAGGGAAUACCCACUUUGCUGUGGUCACAGUGGAGAAGGAACUGUACACUUGGGUGAACAUGCAAGGAGGCACUAAACUCCAUGGUCAGCUGGGCCAUGGAGACAAAGCCUCCUAUCGACAGCCAAAGCAUGUGGAAAAGUUGCAAGGCAAAGCUAUCCGUCAGGUGUCAUGUGGUGAUGAUUUCACUGUCUGUGUGACUGAUGAGGGUCAGCUCUAUGCCUUCGGAUCAGAUUAUUAUGGCUGCAUGGGGGUGGACAAAGUUGCUGGCCCUGAAGUGCUAGAACCCAUGCAGCUGAACUUCUUCCUCAGCAAUCCAGUGGAGCAGGUCUCCUGUGGAGAUAAUCAUGUGGUGGUUCUGACACGAAACAAGGAAGUCUAUUCUUGGGGCUGUGGCGAAUAUGGUAGGGGUAGCCUUGUCUCUGUCCACUUCUUCACAGGACGACUGGGUUUGGAUUCAGAAGAGGAUUAUUAUACACCACAAAAGGUGGAUGUUCCCAAGGCCUUGAUUAUUGUUGCAGUUCAAUGUGGCUGUGAUGGGACAUUUCUGUUGACCCAGUCAGGCAAAGUGCUGGCCUGUGGACUCAAUGAAUUCAAUAAGCUGGGUCUGAAUCAGUGCAUGUCGGGAAUUAUCAACCAUGAAGCAUACCAUGAAGUUCCCUACACAACGUCCUUUACCUUGGCCAAACAGUUGUCCUUUUAUAAGAUCCGUACCAUUGCCCCAGGCAAGACUCACACAGCUGCUAUUGAUGAGCGAGGCCGGCUGCUGACCUUUGGCUGCAACAAGUGUGGGCAGCUGGGCGUUGGGAACUACAAGAAGCGUCUGGGAAUCAACCUGUUGGGGGGACCCCUUGGUGGGAAGCAAGUGAUCAGGGUCUCCUGCGGUGAUGAGUUUACCAUUGCUGCCACUGAUGAUAAUCACAUUUUUGCCUGGGGCAAUGGUGGUAAUGGCCGCCUGGCAAUGACCCCCACAGAGAGACCACAUGGCUCUGAUAUCUGUACCUCAUGGCCUCGGCCUAUUUUUGGAUCUCUGCAUCAUGUCCCGGACCUGUCUUGCCGUGGAUGGCAUACCAUUCUCAUCGUUGAGAAAGUAUUGAAUUCUAAGACCAUCCGUUCCAAUAGCAGUGGCUUAUCCAUUGGAACUGUGUUUCAGAGCUCUAGCCCGGGAGGAGGCGGCGGGGGCGGCGGUGGUGAAGAAGAGGACAGUCAGCAGGAAUCUGAAACUCCUGACCCAAGUGGAGGCUUCCGAGGAACAAUGGAAGCAGACCGAGGAAUGGAAGGUUUAAUCAGUCCCACAGAGGCCAUGGGGAACAGUAAUGGGGCCAGCAGCUCCUGUCCUGGCUGGCUUCGAAAGGAGCUGGAAAAUGCAGAAUUUAUCCCCAUGCCUGACAGCCCAUCUCCUCUCAGUGCAGCGUUUUCAGAAUCUGAGAAAGAUACCCUGCCCUAUGAAGAGCUGCAAGGACUCAAAGUGGCCUCUGAAGCUCCUUUGGAACACAAACCCCAAGUAGAAGCCUCGUCACCUCGGCUGAAUCCUGCAGUAACCUGUGCUGGGAAGGGAACACCACUGACUCCUCCUGCGUGUGCGUGCAGCUCUCUGCAGGUGGAGGUUGAGAGAUUGCAGGGUCUGGUGUUAAAGUGUCUGGCUGAACAACAGAAGCUACAGCAAGAAAACCUCCAGAUUUUUACCCAACUGCAGAAGUUGAACAAGAAAUUAGAAGGAGGGCAGCAGGUGGGGAUGCAUUCCAAAGGAACUCAGACAGCAAAGGAAGAGAUGGAAAUGGAUCCAAAGCCUGACUUAGAUUCAGAUUCCUGGUGCCUCCUGGGAACAGACUCCUGUAGACCCAGCCUCUAGUCUCCUGAGCCUGUAGAGCCCCCAGGAGACUGGGACCCAAAGAACUUCACAGCACACUUACCGAAUGCAGAGAGCAGCUUUCCUGGCUUUGUUCACUUGCAGAAAAGGAGCGCAAGGCAGAGGCUCUGAAGCACUUUCCUUGUACAUUUGGAGAGUGGCAUUGCCUUUUAGAUAGGAUCUAGGAGUGAUUUUAUUGUUUUGGAGAAUGGAAGGGCCCCCAUGGCCCUGGCUUUGUCAUCAGUGACUGCCAUAGCAACAGCAGCUCUGUACCUCAUCUGUUGAUCCCACCUUUGAAGAGGAGACACAGUGCUCACCUUAAUUGCGCUGGUAGCAGCUUAUAUCCCAUGUAUCAUUUUCACCAUUGAUUGGAAGCUGCCUUGGGAAUUCAGUACCAGGCAUUACCCCUCUGGGUGGGAGAGGGAGAAGUGUAAAGUUGGAGUGGGCUGGAAUCAGGUGUGGCCCGCCCAGUGUCCUCUGCAGAGUGGUGAAGUAGUCUGGCCCUCUUGGGAGCCCUGAGUCCAGGAAAAUAUGUCUGAUGGAGUCAAUCUAGGGCUUGUUUCGAAAAAGUUCAGUUACUCUGUGCAGCUAAAUGCUUUAGGAGGAAAGGUAGGCUUAGGUUGCUUUUCCUCUGAGGGUUGAUUGAAAUUUCUUCAGUGAGGAAUAGAGAAAGGGCAGGACCCUCCUCAUCACACAGCUGGUGUUUCAGGCUGUGACCAAUGCAGGGUGGGAUUUCCUAACUGUGGAUGAGGGGAUGAGGUGUCUCUGAGGGAUGAGGUGUCUCAGAGAAUUGAGUCCAUGGGGCAGUCAGAAUAGCCUUAAGAGAAAAUCAUGAAGGAGAAGAGGUCCUCCUUUAGCUGCCUCUACUUGGUAUCUUAGAGAGGGCUUAGAGGGCUCUCAGUCUUCUGCCCAUGAAAAGACUUCUUUGAGCCUCUGCCUUCAUGGCUCUUAGGGUUCUGAUCUUGAUAUCAGCAGCCCCAACCACUUUCUUUCUGAAUGUCUAGUCAGUAUUUUUCCCCUUUUGGUGUUUUAUGAAGCCAUGUGGUAACGAAUGAAUCUGUAUCAUUUUUCCUACCUGAGUGGCCCAAAGCCAGCACCAAACCCUGGGAGUCCCUGAAGCCUAACAGAACAGGUAGAACUUGCAAAAGGAAUUUGGCUGAGAGCUCACUUCUAAUCCUGUACUCACUGUGUCUUUGUAGAUAGAAACAAGCUAGCUUUACCAAAGAGAAAUAGUGUCAUAGAAGAACAAAACUUCAUAUAGAAAGUUCUAGGCAAGUAUUUGAUGGUUUCCUUAAGGAUGUGAGCUUUGUAUUUCCACCUAGCCUUGUAAAAUGUUCCUGUGGUAUUUUGUGUCACACAUCCUACCUUUGAUGAGUCUCACAUCCCACCUUCCUAUAAACAGCUAAAUUAAUUUUGUUUCAUCUUCCCCAGACCAAAAUGUUUGAUAAUCUUAUCAACAUUGUGGGAGGUCUUGUGCAAUGGAAAUUUUGCCAUUUCUCCAAAACUGGUGGCAUAAAGGCUGAUGCUUGGGGAGAACCCCAUUGCUCGGGACAGGCAACUCUGUUCAAUGGGAUCUUCUUUGGUUUGAUGUUCCCAUUGUUUUCUCAGUUCUGGGAAGCCUAGUACAUUAGUACUAAUGUAAUCACUGAAACCUUUUCUUGAAAUAAGGGAAGCAGCCAAACUUUGAUUAAAGUUGCAAGUUCUGGGGACUUGCGGGGGUUGUCAUAAACUGUAACAGUGGGUUUUGGUUCAGCAUGUAAAUGCAACUUUGAUUUUCUUGAGGACCGAUUGACCUGUCAUGUCCCUGUAUCCUCAUGCUCAUCAUCUCAGCAGGCCUGAGAGGCUGGGUCAGUUUGGGUGUUCAUCAUGAGGAUUGCUUCUGCCAUGGAGCUGAUGGACAUGGGCAGGUUGCUGAGAAGGUGGGGUGAAAGUGAGUGCCGGGGGUGGGUGAGUGCCCUGGUCUUGUUCAUAGGGGAGCCUUUCCCUAGCAGUGGAACGCUGUGGUCAUUUUCUCUAGCAUAUUCCCUUGGGAAGUCUAGAUUUGCUAUUAAUCUGGCUGAGAAUCUAAGUUCUGUGCCUUAGAGACAGUUUGCACUUUCCCAUAUUGUGCCUGGGACAGCCAUAUGAUUUUUUUUCCCACCAAACAAGUAUGCAAACAGAAACCAGUUCAAAGGGGGAUGGAGUAAAAGAUGAGGCAGUAGAAAUGCCUUUGAAUGGUUUUCUGUAGCUAAUUCUCUUUAAAUUUUGUCCUGCUUUUUUUCUUUAUGCAGUGCUAGGUGUUUUAAGUUUUCUAGUAGUAUUGCUUUUGAGUUACAGUAUAACCUGAGUUACUCCUCUGCUCUAACAUUGUUGCAGAAGAACUAGUUUAUUGUUAGCCAGGUUGCUUGAAAGGUUGAGAGUGGAGUGGUUUGGCAUUUCUGUUUUAAAUAAACAUUUAAGCUCUUAAUCAGUACUGUGCUUCAGUAAGCCUGUGCAUGGACCUUAGUCUCUGGGGAUAAAACAUCCAGAUUCUAAGCCUCCGUGAAUCUUUGAUUCUGUGAGUCUUUAUAUAAAUAAUGUUCUUGGAACAGAAACAAUGCAAGGGACAUCUGCACAGAAAUAUUCUUUGCUUCUCUCCAGUUUCUUAUUCUUGCCAGCAGAAUCAUUGCUGCUGCUACAGCUUUUUUCCCAAAAAUGUCUAAAAGUGCCGAAAGUGCAGAGGGAGGGAAAAAAUGAGCCACUAAAAGAAGGAUGAUCCUUUCUUGUACCUACCUCCUCAGUCUCAGUGGGGGCCUUUCCAAGUGAUAAUGCCAGUUUAUGGUUUGUAAAACUUUUCCUUCAAAGAGAUUGAACUGAAUUUGGUCUCCCUGGCAUAGCACAGCCAAGUUACAACUUCUCUUGGCUGAGCAUUUCACUGAAGUUUAAAGCAAAAGUACACUAAAAAAUUUCAUUUCACUUGCCAUAUGUUCACAAACAUUCAUAAUAGAACAAUUCAGGGGCAAGAAUACAUUUUAAAUAAAUUCAUUCACAUGAAAUCCCUAAACCUCCAAAAAAGUAUUCAUGAUGGUCAGGGCAGAGUGGGCUAUAAUCAGGACUAUAAAACAUGUUCCUAACUGCUGCAAAGCCAAAAAUCAUUUAUUGUUUCAAUGAUUAACUGUGGAAAUAAACACGCUGAUCAUUAAACCUCACAGAAUGAUGAACAUUAGGGAGAAAAACUCCACUAUGUCACAUCUCUGUUACCACCUGUGUAGCUGUGGAGAGUGAUAAAUUGAUAAUGAAAGCAAACAUUGGCCAGAAGGUGCUGUGCUGCAUUACAUACAUUGCUGUUAAGAAAUACUGUCUCGGGCCAGACGCAGUGGCUCACGCCUGUAAUCCCAGCACUUUGGGAGGCCGAGGCGGGCGGAUCACGAGGUCAGGAGAUCGAGACCAUCCUGGCUAACACAGUGAAAUCCCGUCUCUACUAAAAAUACAAAAAAAUUAGCUGGGUGUUGUGGCAGGUGCCUGUAGUCCCAGCUACUCUGGAGGCUGAGGCAGGAGAAUGGCGUGAACCCAGGAGGCGGAGUUUGCAGUGAGCUGAGAUUGCGCCACGGUACUCCAGCCUGGGCGACAGAGUGAGACUCCAUCUCAAAAAUAAAAAAAAAAAUACUGUCUUGGCAGGACAGGCGCGGUGGCUCACGCCUGUAAUCCCAGCACUUUGGGAGGCCGAGGUGGGCAGGUCAGGAGUUCAAGACCAUCCUGGCUAACACAGUGAAACCCCAUCUCUACUAAAAAUACAAAAAAUCAGCCGGGCGUGGUGGUGGGCGCCUGUAGUCCCAGCUACUCGGGAGGCUGGGGCAGAAGAAUGGCGUGAACCCGGGAGGCGGAGCUUGCAGUGGGCCAAGAUCACUCCACUGCACUCCAGCCUGGGUGACAAGAGCGAGACUCCGUCUCAAAAAAAAAAAAAAAGAAAUACUGUCUCGGCACAUCUGCAUACAUUUUUAAUGAAAUGAGUUUCCACAUGAGGAGUUUCCCCGUGAAAUUUCUCCUAUGGUGUAACCUUAUGAACUUUAUAAUGUUUACUUGCACUAAACAUUUCUUGGAUAAAGUUGUAUAAAAUACAGACAUUAAGAAGCAGCAUGCAUUUACUGUCAUCGUCUGAGCUAUCCAGGAAGAAAUUCAGAUUUUUUUAAAAAAAGGUUCUUAUCUCUUCCCAGAGACCAGAUCAAGAUAAAUUUAAAAGAUGAAAGAUAUUUCUUUUUUUUUUUUCUUUUUUUUUUUUUGAGAUGGAUUCUUACUAGGUCACCAGGCUGGAGUGCAGUGGCGCGAUCUCAGCUCACUGCAACCUCUGCCUCCUGGGUUCAAGCAAUUCUCCUGCCUCAGCCUCCCGAGUAGUUGGGACUACAGGUGUGCGCCACCACGCCCAGCUAAUUUUUGUAUUUUUAGUAGAGACGGGGUUUCACCAUGUUGGCCAGGAUGGUCUCGAUCUCUUGACUUUGUGAUCCGCCCACCUCGGCCUCCCAAAGUGCUGGGAUUACAGGCAUGAGCCACCAUGCUCGGCCUUGAAAGAUAUUUCUAAUAUAACCAAGGCCUAAACAUGUAGAGAUUAAAGGGAACACUUAAGGCAUUGACUAUUGUUUUAUUUCUUUAGCAAAAUGAGAGCAAACAACUGCUUCCUUUUUAGAAAGCACUCCCCACAUAUAACAACAAUUUGUUCUCUCUGGAGGGCCCGGAUCUAUGACCUUACUAACAUCCAGCGAUCCCAAAUCCAAGUGCCUGUGGUACCAGGCAGAUAAGGUAAAGAAGUGAAGCAGGCCAAGUGAGACUGCAGUGGUCUGGUGCUACCAUUCCCAUCUGGAGGAGCAUCUGAUUCUAAACCCCACCCAAUUUGUGCCAUGCGGGUUGCUGGCCCAGUGUUUCCAGAACUUCCAGUUUUUCAAGAGAUGUUCCAUAUCCCAGUUUUUAAAUGUCAGAUCAUAUUAUGAAUGCUAGGCCAGCGAAAUAAAACAUCUGUGGAGCAAAGCAAUCCACAUGUUGCCAUUUUGUGACCUUGGCCACAGCUUACUCUUGCCAUCUAUUGCAAUGUACUGGUUUACAUUCCCACUUAAAGUGUACAUUUCAUUGAACUUGCCUAGGGAAUGUACCUAUUAGGUUAAAUAUCCAUUAUCUCUGUGUGAGGUUUCCUUAAGGGGCUAACCAUAAAGCUUUAUUAUGUGAUACCUCCUUUCCUUUGGAACAAUUAAAAAGAGUGCAAAGAAA